GACGACUCCACAGAGAGACACACAGACACACAUACAUUCCUGGUUAAUGACUCCGGACGUCAGAUGUAGGCAGAGCUGUCACGUACCUACGCUACAGAUCUCUGUGAGGAGUGUGUGUGGAGACUCAAGGGACUAUAGAUCGGGGCAGAAAAUACCGCGGAAGGAAAGACAUUCAGGGGGAAGAAAAGGCAUUCACCCACCCUUGUUCACGGUGGUGACUUGAGCCGUGUGAGGCAGAACUGCAGGGGCAGGUCCUCCAGGGGGCUCGGUUUCCAUCCGUCUCGCCGAAGGGAUAGUCCUGGGUCCUCCGCUGCUGGGAGAGCGCCGCGGUGGCUGGAUGCUGACGUGCUCCGGAGGGUUAAAAGAUGAUCGCCAAAGGCGAACGGGAGUAGCAGUUCGGUGGCCCUCAAGUUACAGGUCGUAACGAUUGCCCAGUGCUCUGGGCUUCUCCAGAAGAGCCUUUGGUCGCGUCCGGGCCAAGCCGUGGGCUAAUGCCGCUCAGGAAAGCUCCGGAGCCCGCCCGCCAGGCAGCCGCAGCCCCGCCGAGCCUCAGAGGCCGUGGGAGCCGGGCUCGGCGCGCGUCUCCGGAGGCUGCCGGGCGUGCGGCGGGCCCCCGAGAAGCCCGUCAUGCCGGCCCCGCCAGGUCCCGGGACUCCCGGCAGCCCGAGGAAGGAGAGUGAUGCGGAAAGCGUCUACGGAGCCCGGACUGCUGGGGCAGCUCGCGGCAGCAUUGCGGCUGCACUGGGCAGCCCCCCCGGGAACUUCCCGCCUACGACCGAGCUCGUUCAGGCUUUCUGCUGUAGGCACUCAUUGAGCUGCUGCCGCCGCUGUCCUUUCCUUCCUUUCCCGGUUUUGUGGGGGCCUCUGGAGAUGGGGAGAGUCCUGGGAAACGUAGGCCAAGUUCUGAGUAGGGAGAGUCGCCGCAGUUCCGGGGCAGCCAGUCCGGUCGCCGUCUCGGCGAGCGCUCAGCAGCCUCGGCGCCCGGUGCCACUUUGCCACCUCUCGCGGUCCCCGGCCUGUGCCCCUUUGCUGCGGACAGGGCAGCCGCCAGCCAGCUGUGCCCUGGAGCAGAGCCUGGCAGCACUGCUUCCUCCUUGGCCGCACCGCUCCCAGUGACAGUUUCUUUUGUAGCUGAUCCCCCCCUAGAUCGCCGGUCCCUGCUCCUUUCACCCCUACAGGCACUUGCGUGUCGCCCCCUUUUUUGCUUUUUUCCUUCACUCCCUCCCUUGCUGCUUUUUUCGCUGAAACAAUUGCUGCUUCUGUUGCCUCUCAGAGAGGGUGCCGGUUUCUUCUCCCUUUUUUCCGACCUCAUCAGCUUUUUUUGAAAAGAAAAAAAUUGAGCGCUUUUUGAGUUGAAAAACCCGCCCCCAUUUUAACGGCAGAGUUUUAAGGAGGCUCGGCAGAGUUGCAGCGCCGCGGGAGCGGGAAGGCCGGGCGCCGCCCACGCCCCGCCCUCCGCCCUGCUGGCGCUCGCGCUCGCAGUCUCGCACGCUCCGCCCGCCCGGUCCCGCGCCCUCAUUCCCGCCUCCCGCUCUCCACCUCCUCCCGUCAAGUCUCUCGCGCCGGCUCCCUCCUGCCGGCUAGGCGGCCUGUCCCCAGCUGGAGCGGGGUUCGGCCCCGCGAAGUCCGGCCUGCCCUUCUGCUGGCGGGCUUGAGUCUGUGACGCGAACCCCCAGCUGCCCCAAUUCCUACGGGGGCGAGGACAGGGGUUUGUUAUUUAAGACGGUUGUGGAGGGCCGCAGGGUCUUUGAGGCUCCGCAGCGUACGCUGCGGGAAGGCGGACAGCGAGCUGGCAUAAAGGGAGUCGUUCCUCAGCGCUAGCGGGGCAGGUCGGCCCGCCUCUGUGCUCCCCCGCCAGGCUCGCAAAGUUCGGGCGGCCAGGCUGCGGCUGCUGCUGCCUCCUCUAGGCGCGCGCGCUCUGUAAACUCGGCGUCCUUCGCUGAGCCCUGGCCUCGGCCUCGCACCUGCCAGAUCCAUGCCCGACGGCGCGGUGGGCAGGGGUGGCCGCGGGGGUGGAGGGAAAAAUCCGGACUGCCACUAAGCACAGUGCUCACAAAAAGCAAGUCUUGUGUAGACUGAAUUUUAUGAAAACUUAAGACAUGGCAUAUGUAAGAACGAACUCUGAAGCCUUAAUUAAUCAAGGACUGGAAACUGCGAAAUAGUCCUAUUAUUAGAGAAAAAGGAGAAAAGCAAUUAAAUUUAAAGCAAAAUUUAAAA